ACCUCCUCCUGAGCGCGGUGACCAGGUCACAGGCUGUCCCUCGUGCCUCAGUGUUCUCAUCUGUAUGUCGAGCACUGCACAGAAUCGGCUCAUGCGCUGAGGCUUUCACGCCUGUGAUGGAAGAGACAGAGAAGGGGGUGGCCUCUCCUCUCCCUGGGGACCUGCCAUUCUCAGCACAGGCACAUGGCAGGCAGCAGCCUCCCUUCUGCCAGCAGAGGGGCUUAAUGCACCCCGUUCCAUUUGUAAUUCAUGUGCAUUGAGCUCACUGGAUGAGUCAGUUGGGAUAUAUAUUCCUCCCUGGGUCUGCCCCAUUUUAUGGGGUGUUGCUUAAUCAUUUGUGUUAUUCCAUUGACAUAAAAUAUUUAGCACUCAGAGAUCAUUUCUGGUCAGGAGAAAUGUGUGCAUUUUUAACCCAAAAUAGAAACCUUCAUAAAAGCAUCAUAGGUCUCCAUUCAAUAUUGACUAUAAUUGUUCACAUGCCCACACUGAAUGCUAACUUGGGCUCACCCUCAACACCCACCAGGUGGGUACUAUUAUUAUCACUCACAUUUGACCAGAGGGAUUGUUUGAUUAGGGUGAAGUAGUUGAGAGUUCAGACCCAGGAGACAGCCUGCCUGCUUCGAAUCCUGGCCCAACCCCUGGCCCUGUGUGACCUUGGGCAAGUGACUGUAUCUCUCUGUGCUAUUGUUUUCUUAUUAAUAAAAUGGGGGAUAUAAUGAUACCUACCUCUUAGGGUUGUUCUCAGCGUUGAGUACAAAUGCCUGCGGAUCAGUGCCUGGCUCAUGGUAAAUGCAUGUCGGUGUUAGCUAGUGUUUUCUUCAGUCUCAAAAUGUUUAAUAAAUGCCUUCCGUGAGCCAGGCACCAUGGAUCGGCAGUACCCAUGAUAGAUGAGGCUCUGCUUGCAUGGGAGAGCCAGAGAAUAAAUGAAUAAACAAGAAAAGACCAGAUGAGAGUGGCUUUAAAGCCAAUAAAACAGGGAAAUGGUGAAUGGAGCAACUGGGGAGAAGUGUCACCAAAGUCAGGGAAUCAGGGAAGCCUUCCCCAAAGAGGUGGCAUUUGAACUGGGACCUGAGUGGUGAAGCAGCCAGCCAUGGGAAGGGUUUGGGGAACAAGAUAUGCAAAGGCCCUGUUGUGGAAAUAAGCCAGCUGUGGUUGAGGAACAACAGCAAGGCAGCCAGUGUGGCUGGAGUGGAGUGAGCAGGGUGGGCCAGUGGUGAGGGAGAACAGGCCAGAGAGGGGGAUUAGCAGCAGGCCUUGUAGGGCCUUUUAUGGCAUAGAAGGAGCUCUGAAGCAAUGAAGUGCCUUGCCAUGUGUCACAUACCAGCCGAGACAGUCUGCCUAACUCGGGAGCCAAAGCUCACUGCUGGGCUUGAGGCCCCUGUAAGAGGACAAUGUAACCCAGGCUGGUAUGGGCACAUUCUGCAUUUCCACUUAAACUCAGAUGGCAAGCCCAUCAAACCUUGGUGCCAUGGCUGCCCUGGUAAUUCCUGGCUGACCAGUGUAACCAGGGAGCUGGCCCAUGACCUGGGUGGCAGCUGAGUAGCCAGGACUAAUGCGACCAAGAGUCAGCCUUCUUCCUGUGACUCAUCCAGGUGCACCCUGCGACAUCUGAAGGUCAGGCUUUCAGCCGCUGUGGCUUCCACUUCCAACUGGCUCCACGUCCCCAGGGAGGGAUCACAUAGAGCUUUGCCAACACAUUCUAUUGCGUGUUUAAUGUUCCUGUGAAUGGGCCCUUGAGAUUUCUCUCUCUCCCAUCCACACAGAGCUUAGAGGCAAAGUUAAGAGACUCAUCAUAUUCUGAGCUGCUGCGGGAUAUUUUGCAGAAGACUGUGAGGCAUCCUGUGUGUGUGAAGCACCCGCCGUCAGUCAAGUAUGCCUGGUUCUUUCUCUCAGAACUCAUCAAAAAGAGACAAGAUCUCUGUUGCCCAGGCUGUCCUCGAACUCCUGGGCUCAAGCAGUCCUCCCACGUCAGCCUUUAGAGUAGCUGGAACUAUUCGACACACACCACCACGCCCAACGAAGUGAGUAUUUUAUAUACCAGCUGGCCGGUAUUAUACCAUUCCAUCCCAAAUCUCCCCUCCAAACUUGGUGAAAAUCAUCUGGCCAUUUUUACAGAUUAGAACGAAAGCAAACAAGCUCUCACUCUGUCUGCCCCCAGCACGAGGCUGUCCACACGGAGCCUUUGGACAAACUGUACGAGGUGCUCGCGGAGACUCUGAUGGCCAAGGAGUCCACCCAGGGCCACCGGAGCUAUUUGCUGUCCUCAGGAGGCUCGGUCACACUCUCCAAGAGCACAGCCAUCAUCUCCCACGGUACCACAGGCCUGGUCACAUGGGAUGCCGCCCUCUACCUUGCAGAAUGGGCCAUCGAGAACCCGGCAGCCUUGAUUAACAGGACUGUCCUAGAGCUUGGCAGUGGUGCCGGCCUCACAGGCCUUGCCAUCUGCAAGAUGUGCCGCCCCCGGGCAUACAUCUUCAGCGACCCUCACAGCCGGGUCCUCGAGCAGCUCCGAGGGAAUGUCCUUCUCAAUGGCCUCUCAUUAGAGGCAGACAUCACUGGCAACUUAGACAGCCCCAGGGUGACAGUGGCCCAGCUGGACUGGGACGUAGCAAUGGUCCAUCAGCUCUCUGCCUUCCAGCCAGAUGUUGUCAUUGCAGCAGACGUGCUGUAUUGCCCAGAAGCCAUCGUGUCGCUGGUCGGGGUCCUGCAGAGGCUGGCUGCCUGCCGGGAGCACAAGCGGGCUCCUGAGGUCUACGUGGCCUUUACCGUCCGCAACCCAGAGACGUGCCAGCUGUUCACCACCGAGCUAGGCCGGGAUGGGAUCAGAUGGGAAGCAGAAGCUCAUCAUGACCAGAAACUGUUUCCCUAUGGAGAGCACUUGGAGAUGGCAAUGCUGAACCUCACACUGUAGGACUCACACAUGACUCCAAAGGGAUUGUGAGAAUCAAGUCACUCUCGUGGGAAGAAUUUUUAUAUGGGAAAGUGGAUAAAACUUUCAUUGGACUGGAAUGUUUGGAGAUUAUUAAAUUCCAAAUCAGGAAUCAAAACUGCCCUCUAAUAAGACAUUAGCUGUCUAGGCGUGUGGGUGCCCCCUUUCUGCCAGCAGUUCUGGUUCUCAAGAAAAUCAUCAUAAAUCAGACAUGAAAAUUCUGGCUCCAAAAAUAGCAUUUUCUUUCUGCAAAUAAAAACGUGUGUAUCAAGGAUGACGUUCCCCCAACGUGGACACACUCGGUUCCUCAGAAAGCCAAGCCCGCUGCAGCUGCCACAUCCCUGGACACACUCGGUUCCUCACAAAGCCAAGCCCGCUGCAGCUGCCACAUCCCAGGGCUUAUGGUGCAGCAGGCGCUUUUUUCAAGACAGGAAUGAAAGUGUUAGGAACAUGGCAGAAAGGUGACACCUGGAGACCAAAUGCAGGAUGAGGAGUACUGCAGAGGUCACAGGGAAGUCACAGAACAGUAAUACGCUAGCAGGGGCAUGGGGCAUGAAGAACAGAAGACAGGAAGCAUUUCAGAGACUCCAAAGAAGAAAUCAGGGCCAACCACAGCUUCCCGGGUCAUUCACCAGGUGACACCACUGCCGUCAUUUCAGCUUCUGGCCACUGGGAGGCGCUGCUCGAAAGGCUUUGCCCUGAGACUCCAAGAAGCUGCGGGAAGGACAGCAGGGGCCCUGGGGUUUUAGCCUCUGGCCCAGGAGUUAUGUGUCCAUAACCAAAGGGAGCACAGUCUGCACCCAGCUCUCAUCCCAUCAGAGCUGCUGAGACUCUUGCAGGUUCUUCCAGAACUGGUUUAGCUUGCCUGCAGGAUCAGAAAAGUUUGAGAAAAGCAUCUGCAAAAUGCUAAAGAGCAGAGCUUAACUCAUUGCCUGUCCCCACCCCAUCCCAGGUCACCACUUGGAUGACCCCAGGUCCCCGACCCAACAACAACCCCUCCCAAGUCCCUAACUCCCUCACUUGGACUUGAGACCCUUCACAACCCCCCUCACUUGGACUUGAGACCCUUCACAACCCAGCAGCGCUCCACCUCCAACUUGACAUCAUGCUUUCUGGAAACUUCCCCGUAUGUCCCACUUUCCCACACUUGGUGCCCUGGAGCACCUUCCGGCCUCUACAUGCUGUACGUUCCCCUGUGAGCACCCUCCUCUCGGCCUCUGGCCAACACAGUCCCACCCAUCUGUGGGUAACAAGGGGGUGUGGGUGUUCUUUUCAGCCUUGCUAAACUGUCUGAAUCAAGGAUCACAAACUACAGCCUGCAGGCCAAAUCCAGCCCACAGCCUGUGUUUGUGAAUAAAGCUUUGUUGGAACAAAGCCACA